CUCACGUGGCCAGCCCCCUCCGAGAGGGGAGACCAGCGGGCCAUGACAAGCUCCAGGCUUUGGUUUUCGCUGCUGCUGGCGGCAGCGUUCGCAGGACGGGCGACGGCCCUCUGGCCCUGGCCUCAGAACUUCCAAACCUCCGACCAGCGCUACGUCCUUUACCCGAACAACUUUCAAUUCCAGUACGAUGUCAGCUCGGCCGCGCAGCCCGGCUGCUCAGUCCUCGACGAGGCCUUCCAGCGCUAUCGUGACCUGCUUUUCGGUUCCGGGUCUUGGCCCCGUCCUUACCUCACAGGUUGGCCGCACCAAGCUUACCCUGUCUUCCUAGGGAAACGGCAUACACUGGAGAAGAAUGUGUUGGUUGUCUCUGUAGUCACACCUGGAUGUAACCAGCUUCCUACUUUGGAGUCAGUGGAGAAUUAUACCCUGACCAUAAAUGAUGACCAGUGUUUACUCCUCUCUGAGACUGUCUGGGGAGCUCUCCGAGGUCUGGAGACUUUUAGCCAGCUUGUUUGGAAAUCUGCUGAGGGCACAUUCUUUAUCAACAAGACUGAGAUUGAGGACUUUCCCCGCUUUCCUCACCGGGGCUUGCUGUUGGAUACAUCUCGCCAUUACCUGCCACUCUCUAGCAUCCUGGACACUCUGGAUGUCAUGGCGUACAAUAAAUUGAACGUGUUCCACUGGCAUCUGGUAGAUGAUCCUUCCUUCCCAUAUGAGAGCUUCACUUUUCCAGAGCUCAUGAGAAAGGGGUCCUACAACCCUGUCACCCACAUCUACACAGCACAGGAUGUGAAGGAGGUCAUUGAAUACGCACGGCUCCGGGGUAUCCGUGUGCUUGCAGAGUUUGACACUCCUGGCCACACUUUGUCCUGGGGACCAGGUAUCCCUGGAUUACUGACUCCUUGCUACUCUGGGUCUGAGCCCUCUGGCACCUUUGGACCAGUGAAUCCCAGUCUCAAUAAUACCUAUGAGUUCAUGAGCACAUUCUUCUUAGAAGUCAGCUCUGUCUUCCCAGAUUUUUAUCUUCAUCUUGGAGGAGAUGAGGUUGAUUUCACCUGCUGGAAGUCCAACCCAGAGAUCCAGGACUUUAUGAGGAAGAAAGGCUUCGGUGAGGACUUCAAGCAGCUGGAGUCCUUCUACAUCCAGACGCUGCUGGACAUCGUCUCUUCUUAUGGCAAGGGCUAUGUGGUGUGGCAGGAGGUGUUUGAUAAUAAAGUAAAGAUUCAGCCAGACACAAUCAUACAGGUGUGGCGAGAGGAUAUUCCAGUGAACUAUAUGAAGGAGCUGGAACUGGUCACCAAGGCCGGCUUCCGGGCCCUUCUCUCUGCCCCCUGGUACCUGAACCGUAUAUCCUAUGGCCCUGACUGGAAGGAUUUCUACAUAGUGGAACCCCUGGCAUUUGAAGGUACCCCUGAGCAGAAGGCUCUGGUGAUUGGUGGAGAGGCUUGUAUGUGGGGAGAAUAUGUGGACAACACAAACCUGGUCCCCAGGCUCUGGCCCAGAGCAGGGGCUGUUGCCGAAAGGCUGUGGAGCAACAAGUUGACAUCUGACCUGACAUUUGCCUAUGAACGUUUGUCACACUUCCGCUGUGAAUUGCUGAGGCGAGGUGUCCAGGCCCAACCCCUCAAUGUAGGCUUCUGUGAGCAGGAGUUUGAACAGACCUGAGCCCCAGGCACCGAGGAGGGUGCUGGCUGUAGGUGAAUGGUAGUGGAGCCAGGCUUCCACUGCAUCCUGGCCAGGGGACGGAGCCCCUUGCCUUCGUGCCCCUUGCCUGCGUGCCCCUGUGCUUGGAGAGAAAGGGGCCGGUGCUGGCGCUCGCAUUCAAUAAAGAGUAAUGUGGCAUUUUUCUAUAAUAAACAUGGAUUACCUGUGUUUAAAAAAAAAAGUGUGAAUGGCGUUAGGGUAAGGGCACAGCCAGGCUGGAGUCAGUGUCUGCCCCUGAGGUCUUUUAAGUUGAGGGCUGGGAAUGAAACCUAUAGCCUUUGUGCUGUUCUGCCUUGCCUGUGAGCUAUGUCACUCCCCUCCCACUCCUGACCAUAUUCCAGACACCUGCCCUAAUCCUCAGCCUGCUCACUUCACUUCUGCAUUAUAUCUCCAAGGCGUUGGUAUAUGGAAAAAGAUGUAGGGGCUUGGAGGUGUUCUGGACAGUGGGGAGGGCUCCAGACCCAACCUGGUCACAGAAGAGCCUCUCCCCCAUGCAUACUCAUCCACCUCCCUCCCCUAGAGCUAUUCUCCUUUGGGUUUCUUGCUGCUUCAAUUUUAUACAACCAUUAUUUAAAUAUUAUUAAACACAUAUUGUUCUCUAGGCACUGUGGUAGUGGGUUUUUUUGUUGUUUUUGUUUUUGAGACUGUCUCAAAAACUCUGUCGCCCAGGCUGACAGUGCAGUGGCACAAUCUUGGCUCACUGCAGCCUCUGCCUCCUGGGUUCAAGCGAUUCUCGUGCAUCAGCCUCCUGAGUAACUGGAAUUAAUAGGCACGUGCCACCAUGUCCAUCUAAUUCAUAUAUAUAUAUUUUUUUUUUCUGAGACGGAGUCUCACUGUCACACAGGCUGGAGUGCAGUGGCACGAUCUCGACUCACUGCAAGCUCCACCUCCUGGGUUCACGCCAUUCUCCUGCCUCAGCCUCCCCAGUAGCUGGGACUACAGGCGCCCGCCACCACGCCCGGCUAAUUUUUUGUAUUUUUAGUAGAGAUGGGGUUUCUCCGUGUUAGCCAGGAUGGUCUCGAUCUCCUGACCUCGUGAUCCGCCCGCCUUGGCCUCCCAAAGUGCUGGGAUUACAGGCGUGAGCCACCGCGCCCGGCCGAAUUCAUCUAUUUUUAGUAGAGAUGGGGUUUCACUAUAUUGGCCAGGCUGGUCUUGAACUCAUGACCUCAGAUGUUCACUUGUCUUGGCCUCCCAAAGUGCUGGGAUUAGAGGCGUGAGCCACCGCACGCGGGCCUGUGGUAAAUUGUUGAAUUUGAAGGACUCAGAGGCCCUGGUCAAUUCCAAAAUAACGUAGGCGACUUCCAUCCCCCUCCUCCCAACCAUUUUCAGCCCAAAGCAUCUUCGCAGGGAAUGGAUGGCUGCGCGGAGGUGGGCGGUGGCUCUGGAGAGGGUCUUUGCAGGUGUGAUUUUCUCUAGAAGGAAAUGUCUCGUCGUGGACCCAGACUGCCCCCUCCUGGUUUCAGAUGCAGAAGUGAUACUGUAAGCCAGAGGCGGGGGCAGUAAUGCAUCGCAGCCAUUUUAGGUGAGGAUUUCCUUGGCGGUUAUUUGUUAAGUUCUUUGGCUGGGCCCUGGGCUGGGGUAACAAUGGACAGGUUCCAGGCAUUUUUUUCAGAAAGCUUCCAGUGUAGUGGAUACAGAAACUUCAGGAAGGCAGGGCUGAGAAGGAUCUGAGUAAAACUCGGUCCUUCAACACCAUCCUUCAGCCCCUGGGUCAUGUUCCUUCGAGGUCCUGGUGGGAGGUAGACAAGCCUAGCCUUGUGCUGUUCCUGUAAGGACAGGGUGGGCAUUUUCUACCAACAGAAUUCUUGGAAUUUUCACACAGCCCAGCCUAGCCAAGUCCAGGGCUAUAGCCCAGAUACACAAGUUAAGGUCCCAGCACUGGCACCCACCACAGGAGCCCCCUUACCUCUAUUACCCAGAAGCUUGUAGGAGGGGUGGUCCGCAGACAAGGACCCUGCACAGGUGCGACCCUGCUUCCCUCCUGGUCAUAACUUUCAUGUUACUAUUGCUUGGGAUAAUGUUAAGUAAAAAUAGCAGACACUGAGUUUUAAGUCUCAAGUGGAUGAAGGCAGAGAUCGUGAUACACUUGAGUUAAAGCAGUAGGGUUCUGUCAUUUUCUAUUCCUGUUGUAAACAUUUUCUUUAAUGUUAUUAUUUUUACCACUAAACUAACGUGGCCUGGUCACGACUUUCAUUGGUAAAGUGUGCUGUUCCUCACCCUCCACCGUUGCUCCUUUGGUCCACUGAUCAUAAGAGCAUUUACCUGAAGGUCGUCAGACCUCGAAUGCCAACAGGUCAACUGCAGUGGCCUGCAGUUACCACCCAGUCUGUUCCAAUGAACAGAAUCGCUGUUGCCCCAACUCAUCUCCCUUCACCUAGGCUGUAAAUUGAAAGUCCCACCCCUGAGCGGAACACAGGCCAUCUUGUGUGCUGUGCACCACCAGGGGGUGGGGAAGUUUCCAGACUGACUUCCUGGCUCCAGUCAUCCUAGGAAAAGAGUUCUCCAGUCGCUCCCCACCCCCACCCCUUCCCAUUCCAGGAGUCUAUUAAGGAGGCAAAGCAGGCCUAACGGGUAUCAAAGCAAAGGAGUGAAUGGAGACUGGGAGAGUCUUCAACCUCUCCUCUCCUUGGUAGGAGCUGAGGCUGCAUGCCAGGUACCUUCCCUUCGAGGAAUCUAAUAAAGCUAGGUCACUGGUGUUUUCAGGUGCUUCUCAAAGGAUUGCCGUAGGGGUAGGAUAUCAGGAUGUGGGAGCACAGGUGCCACCACAGCACUAGUGAUGGAGAGUCAUUGCCCCUAGACUUCUGGGACAGUGAGACUGUGAGGAAAGCUGAAAUGAUACUGGGAAAGGGUGAAAGAAAGGAUGUAGGUGGAAUUUAUUUAGUAUUAAUGUAGGUACACAUACCUUAUGGCAACAUUCCUAGCACUCUAAAUUCUAGAUUUGUAUAGUUUCUGUCAAUAUCUUUUGUAAGCUUAAUCAAUACAGGGCAUGACAAGUAUGUGUCACAUACUUUUUUUUCCACGAAGAAAAAAAAUAAGUAGGAAUUGGGUGCUUUGUUUAUCAAAAUUUGUAUUUCCUUUAUAAAUAAACUUUGAAAUAAAGGUUGAAAAUUAGUA